UUCUUUAUAUGUCUGGUAGAAUUUGGCUGUGAAUCCAUCUGGUCCAGGGCCUUUUCUGGUUGCAAAAAGAAGAAAGUACUCCUUGAAUAGGAAUUCAGGGACAAUGUUCUAUAUGUACCCAACUUAUGGUUUGGGACAGAACUUACAGAUCUGCCACAACCAGAAGCAUGACUAAGAUCUGCAUAAUUGACUGGUUUUGCUCACCACCUACUCACUGUGCAGGGGCUCCAUGGUUCCUAGAGGCAAGGAAGAAGAGCCACCAGUCAAAUAGGUUUCAGCACCUCCAACUCCAACAUCUUCAAAGCAGCGACUGGGAAGAAAAAUAAUCCUUCUGACAACACAUAUUCAGACACAUAUGGUCAGCCUCAUGAAGCUCUGGAUACCCAUGCUCAUGACAUUCUUCUGUACGGUGCUACUGUCUGUGCUGGGAGAAAUGAGGAAGAAAAGAUAUGACAGGAAGGAAUUGUUACUUGAAGAAUGCUGGGGAAAGCCAAAUGUCAAAGAAUGUACCAAUAAGUGUUCUAAAGCCUUUAGAUGUAAAGACAAAAAUUACACAUGCUGCUGGACCUAUUGUGGAAACAUCUGCUGGAUAAACGUCGAAACCAGUGGAGAUUACUAAAACCGUAGCUUCCCACCAGGCUGCCACCUGUGUGGGCUGGGAAAUGUUUAAGAGGUCUCAUAGUAGUACCCUGUGGCUACUUUUAGGAACACCAGUCUAUUUUUACUGAGAGCUGGACAACAGCAAACACUUGACAAAUAAACUUAUUUACCAGUA